ACCUGCAAAGCAAAGGACGUAGUGUUGAAAACGAGACCAGAAAUGGUGCUGUUAAAGAGCCUUGAAUUAUCAUCACCUGGACCUGUUGUUACAUCAAGAAUCUCUCAUUUCUAAUGUUCUACUUUGGACACUGUUACCUGUGUGGUGGCUUGCACCUCCAAUGCCAGCAGUUUGGGAGCCUGAGGCGGGCAGAAGGCUUGAGCCCAGGAGCUCGAGACCAGCCUGGGCAAUAUGAAGAGACCCUGUCUCUACAAAAAUACCAAAGUUAGCUAGGCCUGGUGGCCUGCAGUCACAAUCACCCGGAAGGUGGAAGUGGAAAGAUCGCUUGAGCUUGGGAGGUUGAGGCUGCAGUGAGUCCUUGAUCGCACCACUACACUCCAGCCUGGACAACAGAACCAGACCGUGUCUCAAUAAACAAUGAUAGGAAUUUAAAAAAAAACUAUUAUAUUUGGCAAAAAGAAAGUUAAAUAUAGUACUUUUGGUGGACCGUUGGGGAUGAAAGCCUGACUGGUUAAGCACCCUGAGAAUGGAGACAGUGUUUGAAGAGAUGGAUGAAGAAAGCACAGGAGGAGUUUCAUCUUCGAAAGAAGAAAUAGUCCUUGGCCAGAGACUCCAUCUAAGCUUUCCUUUUAGCAUUAUCUUCUCAACUGUUCUCUACUGUGGUGAGGUUGCCUUUGGUUUAUACAUGUUUGAAAUUUAUCGAAAAGCUAAUGACACAUUCUGGAUGUCAUUUACCAUCAGCUUUAUUAUUGUGGGGGCAAUUUUGGAUCAAAUUAUCCUGAUGUUUUUCAACAAAGACUUGAGGAGAAAUAAGGCUGCAUUACUUUUUUGGCACAUUCUUCUUUUAGGACCUAUUGUGAGGUGUUUGCACACCAUUAGAAAUUACCACAAAUGGUUGAAAAAUCUUAAACAGGAGAAGGAAGAGACUCAAGUUAGCAUCACAAAGAGAAACACGAUGCUGGAAAGGGAGAUUGCAUUCUCAAUCCGGGAUAAUUUCAUGCAGCAGAAGGCUUUCAAGUACAUGUCAGUGAUUCAGGCUUUUCUCGGUUCUGUUCCACAAUUAAUUUUGCAGAUGUAUAUCAGUCUCACUAUACGAGAAUGGCCUUUGAAUAGAGCAUUGCUGAUGACAUUUUCCCUGUUAUCAGUUACUUAUGGGGCCAUUCGCUGCAAUAUACUGGCCAUCCAGAUCAGCAAUGAUGAUACUACCAUUAAGCUACCGCCGAUAGAAUUCUUCUGUGUCGUGAUGUGGCGUUUUUUGGAGGUUAUCUCACGUGUAGUGACUCUGGCAUUUUUCAUUGCAUCUCUGAAACUGAAGAGCCUACCCGUUUUGUUAAUCAUAUAUUUUGUAUCAUUGUUGGCACCGUGGCUGGAGUUUUGGAAAAGUGGAGCUCAUCUUCCUGGCAACAAAGAAAAUAAUUCCAAUAUGGUGGGUACAGUACUGAUGCUUUUCUUGAUCACACUGCUAUAUGCUGCCAUCAACUUCUCCUGCUGGUCAGCAGUGAAACUGCAGUUGUCAGAUGACAAAAUAAUUGACGGGAGACAGAGGUGGGGCCAUAGAAUCCUACACUACAGCUUUCAGUUUUUAGAAAAUGUGAUAAUGAUAUUGGUAUUUAGGUUCUUUGGAGGGAAAACUUUGCUGAAUUGUUGUGACUCAUUAAUUGCCGUGCAGCUCAUCAUAAGCUACCUAUUGGCCACUGGCUUUAUGCUCCUCUUCUAUCAGUAUUUGUACCCAUGGCAGUCAGGCAAAGUGUUGCCAGGACGUACUGAAAAUCAGCCAGAAGCACCGUACUAUUAUGUAAACAUCGAGAAAACUGAAAAGAAUAAAAAUAAGCAGCUGAGGAAUUACUGUCACUCCUGCAAUAGGGUUGGAUAUUUUUCAAUCAGAAAAAGUAUGACAUGUUCAUAAAAUAUACAUAUAUACUUUCACAGAACAAUGAGUAAAGAUGCUGAAUGUGACUUGUUAAGAGGCUCUUAAAUUUAAAAAAUAUACACAGCAAAAUCUUGGAAGUGGUUUCUAAUAAAAUUCAUUUAUGUUCUCCUGUGAA